GGAACACCUCGGGUCACCCCCGACAACGGUGGUGGGAGGGAGAGCGGCCUCCUCCUCCCUGGUGGGGCCUGUCUGGGUGAAGCCCCUCUGUUCCCGAGGAUCGUCUGCCUUAUUGAAACCAUCUAAUUGGAGAUCCGCAGAUUAGGCUACCAAGACACAGCUGCCUCCAGCAGAAUUUGUGUAGUGGACACUUGUACGUGCACUUUGGAGACAGCAAGCAUGAGGCCUGCAGCUGACAGCUUUGAGUGGCUGUGAACCUGACUAUGGAAAAGAUGUGACUCCCCACCCCCAGCCGGGUGCUCCGAGCCAUGGCCGACACCAUCUUCGGCAGCGGGAAUGAUCAGUGGGUUUGCCCCAAUGACCGGCAGCUUGCCCUUCGAGCCAAGCUGCAGACGGGCUGGUCCGUGCACACCUACCAGACGGAGAAGCAGAGGAGGAAGCAGCACCUCAGCCCGGCGGAGGUGGAGGCCAUCCUGCAGGUCAUCCAGAGGGCAGAGCGGCUCGACGUCCUGGAGCAGCAGAGAAUCGGGCGGCUGGUGGAGCGGCUGGAGACCAUGAGGCGGAAUGUGAUGGGGAACGGCCUGUCCCAGUGUCUGCUCUGCGGGGAGGUGCUGGGCUUCCUGGGCAGCUCGUCGGUGUUCUGCAAAGACUGCAGGAAGGUCUGGAGGGGGAUGGGGGCCUGGCCCUGGGAGGUGUUUGCAGGAGUCCAGCCAGGCCCUGGGUCUGGUCAGUCCACCGCGCCCGGCUAAUUUUUGUAUUUUUAGUAGAGACGGGGUUUCGCCUUGUUGGCCAGGUUGGUGUUGAACUCCUGACCUCAGGCGAUCCGCCCACCUCAGCCUCCCAAAUUGCUGGGAUUACAGGCGUGAGCCACCGCGCCCGACCAGAUUUGCUGGUUUUUAAAAACCCUC